AAUAAACAGGGCAGCUUGGAAGAGGUACCUGCUUUCUAAUAAUUGCCUUUAGUGGGAACAGAAGUCUCCUUUCAAGAAGCUUUUAAUUCAUUUUAAGAUUUAAUUUUAUGUUUUCUGAAGAACAACAAAAAAUAUUUCUGGAAAAGACUGCUGAGAAGAUUUCCCUCUUUCAGCCAGAAGAGCAGAGAGAAGAUUGUAAAUCAAGGAAAAGAUUUCCCCCUUCAGAUCUAACGAUUACAUUAGGGCUCCUGCAUCUUUUUGGAAGGAUUCUUUUUAUAAAUCAGAAAGUGUUCGAGGUUCAAAGGUUUGCCUCGGAGCGUGUGAACAUUCCUCCGCUCGGUUUUCAACUCGCCUCCAACCUGCGCCGCCCGGCCAGCAUGUCUCCCCGCCCGUGAAGCGGGGCUGCCGCCUCCCUGCCGCUCCGGCUGCCACUAACGACCCGCCCUCGCCGCCACCUGGCCCUCCUGAUCGACGACACACGCACUUGAAACUUGUUCUCAGGGUGUGUGGAAUCAACUUUCCGGAAGCAACCAGCCCACCAGAGGAGGUAGACAGACAGCUAUGUAUAUAUAUGUGGGUUUCGCUACAAGUGGCUCUGGAACGAAAGGGCCUGGUUCGCAAAGAAGCUGACUUCAGAGGGGGAAACUUUCUUCUUUUAGGAGGCGGUUAGCCCUGUUCCACGAACCCAGGAGAACUGCUGGCCAGAUUAAUUAGACAUUGCUAUGGGAGACGUGUAAACACACUACUUAUCAUUGAUGCAUAUAUAAAACCAUUUUAUUUUCGCUAUUAUUUCAGAGGAAGCGCCUCUGAUUUGUUUCUUUUUUCCCUUUUUGCUCUUUCUGGCUGUGUGGUUUGGAGAAAGCACAGUUGGAGUAGCCGGUUGCUAAAUAAGUCCCGAGCGCGAGCGGAGACGAUGCAGCGGAGACUGGUUCAGCAGUGGAGCGUCGCGGUGUUCCUGCUGAGCUACGCGGUGCCCUCCUGCGGGCGCUCGGUGGAGGGUCUCAGCCGCCGCCUCAAAAGAGCUGUGUCUGAACAUCAGCUCCUCCAUGACAAGGGGAAGUCCAUCCAAGAUUUACGGCGACGAUUCUUCCUUCACCAUCUGAUCGCAGAAAUCCACACAGCUGAAAUCAGAGCUACCUCGGAGGUGUCCCCUAACUCCAAGCCCUCUCCCAACACAAAGAACCACCCCGUCCGAUUUGGGUCUGAUGAUGAGGGCAGAUACCUAACUCAGGAAACUAACAAGGUGGAGACGUACAAAGAGCAGCCGCUCAAGACACCUGGGAAGAAAAAGAAAGGCAAGCCCGGGAAACGCAAGGAGCAGGAAAAGAAAAAACGGCGAACUCGCUCUGCCUGGUUAGACUCUGGAGUGACUGGGAGUGGGCUAGAAGGGGACCACCUGUCUGACACCUCCACAACGUCGCUGGAGCUCGAUUCACGGAGGCAUUGAAAUUUUCAGCAGAGACCUUCCAAGGACAUAUUGCAGGAUUCUGUAAUAGUGAACAUAUGGAAAGUAUUAGAAAUAUUUAUUGUCUGUAAAUACUGUAAAUGCAUUGGAAUAAAACUGUCUCCCCCAUUGCUCUAUGAAACUGCACAUUGGUCAUUGUGAAUAUUUUUUUUUUGCCAAGGCUAAUCCAAUUAUUAUUAUCACAUUUACCAUAAUUUAUUUUGUCCAUUGAUGUAUUUAUUUUGUAAAUGUAUCUUGGUGCUGCUGAAUUUCUAUAUUUUUUGUAACAUAAUGCACUUUAGAUAUACAUAUCAAGUAUGUUGAUAAAUGACACAAUGAAGUGUCUCUAUUUUGUGGUUGAUUUUAAUGAAUGCCUAAAUAUAAUUAUCCAAAUUGAUUUUCCUUUGUGCAUGUAAAAAUAACAGUAUUUUAAAUUUGUAAAGAAUGUCUAAUAAAAUAUAAUCUAAUUACAUCAUGA